AGUCAGAGCUGCUCGUCUGAGGCUGCUGAGGCGACGGCCGGUGUCGUGGUCGCGGUACCUGUUCCAACACGGCUCGCGGGCCCGUGCCGGCUCCGGUCCCCGGCGCGGCUGUCCGAGCCCCUGCGGCGGGCGGACGAUGGUGUGGCGGAGCACGCGGACGCGGGCGGCGCGGCGGCGGGCAUGAAGGAGGAUGGAAGGGCAGGACGAGGUGUCGGCGCGGGAGCAGCACUUCCACAGCCAAGUGCGGGAGUCCACGAUAUGUUUCCUUCUUUUUGCCAUUCUCUACGUUGUUUCCUACUUCAUCAUCACAAGAUACAAGAGAAAAUCAGGAUCUCCUUCUGUCCCCUAGGCCGGAGAGCAGUGGGGCAAUCAUGGCUGACUGUAGCCUCGACCUCCUGGGCUCAAGUGAUUCUCCAACCUCAGCCUCCUGAGUAUCCUGCACUACAGAUGAACAAGAAGAUGAAGAUGCCAUCGUCAACAGGAUUUCGUUGUUUUUGAGCACGUUCACUCUCGCAGUGUCAGCUGGGGCUGUUUUGCUUUUACCCUUCUCAAUCAUCAGCAAUGAAAUCCUGCUUUCUUUUCCUCAGAACUACUAUAUUCAGUGGCUAAAUGGCUCCCUGAUUCAUGGUUUGUGGAAUCUUGCUUCCCUUUUUUCCAACCUUUGUUUAUUUGUAUUGAUGCCCUUUGCCUUUUUCUUUCUGGAAUCAGAAGGCUUUGCUGGCCUGAAAAAGGAGGGCAAGAUGUCCAGGCAAAACCUUGUUUAAAUGUUCAUCACCAUAGAAACAUGACAGCUUCUCCAUAGAGCUUUUGGAAUCCGAGCCCGCAUUUUAGAGACUUUGGUCAUGCUUCUUCUUCUUGCGUUACUCAUUCUUGGGAUAGUGUGGGUAGCUUCAGCACUCAUUGACAACGAUGCCGCAAGCAUGGAAUCUUUAUAUGAUCUCUGGGAGUUCUAUCUACCCUAUUUAUAUUCCUGUAUAUCAUUGAUGGGAUGUUUGUUACUUCUCUUGUGUACACCAGUUGGCCUUUCUCGUAUGUUCACAGUGAUGGGUCAGUUGCUAGUGAAGCCAACAAUUCUUGAAGACCUGGAUGAACAAAUUUAUAUCAUUACCUUAGAGGAAGAAGCACUCCAGAGACGACUAAAUGGGCUGUCUUCAUCGGUGGAAUACAACAUAAUGGAGUUGGAACAAGAACUUGAAAAUGUAAAGACUCUUAAGACAAAAUUAGAGAGGCGAAAAAAGGCUUCAGCAUGGGAAAGAAAUUUGGUGUAUCCCGCUGUUAUGGUUCUCCUUCUUAUUGAGACAUCCAUCUCGGUCCUCUUGGUGGCUUGUAAUAUUCUUUGCCUAUUGGUUGAUGAAACAGCAAUGCCAAAAGGAACAAGGGGGCCUGGAAUAGGAAAUGCCUCUCUUUCUACGUUUGGUUUUGUGGGAGCUGCGCUUGAAAUCAUUUUGAUUUUCUAUCUUAUGGUGUCCUCUGUUGUCGGCUUCUAUAGCCUUCGAUUUUUUGGAAACUUUACUCCCAAGAAAGAUGACACAACUAUGACAAAGAUCAUUGGAAAUUGUGUGUCCAUCUUGGUUUUGAGCUCUGCUCUGCCUGUGAUGUCGAGAACACUGGGAAUCACUAGAUUUGAUCUACUUGGCGACUUUGGAAGGUUUAAUUGGCUGGGAAAUUUCUAUAUUGUAUUAUCCUACAAUUUGCUUUUUGCUAUUGUGACAACAUUGUGUCUGGUCCGAAAAUUCACCUCUGCAGUUCGAGAAGAACUUUUCAAGGCCCUAGGGCUUCAUAAACUUCACUUACCAAAUACUUCAAGGGAUUCAGAAACAGCCAAGCCUUCUGUAAAUGGGCAUCAGAAAGCACUGUGAGACGCACAGACGGCGUCUUCUGCCACCAAGAGACCCGAGAACUCCAGAUUCACGACAUUCCUGUCCCAUGUAGAAGCAUUUCCAUUCAACCGUGGCCCCUCUUCAGAACCUAGACCUAUCAGUGCCAUUUUUUUUUCAUAAUCUACGAAGAACUUGGCUAUGGCUGAUCUUUUUUAAAUUUAACUUUCUGAUGGACCCUGUAGUUUCCAGUUAAGUGCAGAUUCCUUACAGACAUAUAGAACAGCGCAUUCUUCUGUAGACAUUUGCUCAUGUUGGUAAAUACAAUCACCCAUAUGAAAAAAUUGUUUUCACCUGAUAUGAAAAUGUUAGAAAAGGCAAACUCCGGGACUUCUAAAGAUUUACUUAAAUCCCAUUAUGUACUUUAUUCAGAAUGUAGAAGCUGACUUGAAAGGCAUCCUUGGUACUAAGUGAAGCUUAUUCAGAAAAUGCAUUUUUCAAAUGCAAUGGCAACUGCUUGUAGAUAUCAUUUUUGCAGUGUAUGUUGGAGCUGUAAUGGUUGCAAUUAUGUUUCUUAUUUCCUUAAAAGCAAAAAGCGUAGUUUCUGAUUUAUGUUAUAGAAUGAUACUGAUUAGACUUUGAGCCAAGGGGAAAAUACUAAAUUCUUUUAAACCUGGAGCCUUAGAGAGCCACAGGAAUAUCUUCUGUUGUACAGUCUAAUAAGCUGUGGUAGGAAGUAUCAUGUAAUCACAGUUUAAUGACAGUUUAUGUAUAUAUAUAAUUCAGUAUUCCCUCUGAUAACAUAGUUGCCAGUGUUUAAUACACUUGUAACUUGGAUUUUUACCUUAUAGGCUAUAUGUAUACUCAGUUUUUUAAAGCAUUUUUUUCAGAGAUCACUUAAUUCCCCAUGCUUCUGCAAUGCAUAUAAAAACUAUAAAUGCCGAGUGGUAGAAACUCCUCUUUCUUCAUAGUCCUCAGGCUUUGGUUACAUUUGCAUAUGCCAUUUGAAGCCUCCAGCUUUUACCAGUUUAACAUCCAAAGUUCACAGCAUCAGCAUUCAUGGUGUAAGAACAGUUUUGCAGUAUAACACGAUCUGAUAAUCAUUCAGUUAUUAAAUUGUAAAUAAUUAUUGGGAUGGUUUCUUGGCUUUAAGUCCACUGAAUAAAAACUAUGAAAUUGCACUCUGUGUCAACCAUCCACUAGGAUAGAAUACCGAAAUCUGUGCAUGCAAAAAUAGGAGAUGGGCCCAUUUGCACACAAUUCGUAGUUAUGCAGUCUGCUAUAUAAAUAUGUUCACAUGCACUGUGUGUAUGAAAAUAGAUGGUCUGUGUUCAGACAAAAGUAAAACAUUUUUUUCAAAUUGUUACAUUUAAAGGUUUUCUGGGAGAAAUUUAUGAAACGCAGGCUGUGUCUAUUUGACAUCAGAAAUUUCCACUUUAAACCAAAAUAAUAAGAAACUUUAAUCUGUAUAUUUACAACCUUUGUUGAGUACACUUCCCCCUUAUUUAUACGUCUGCAUUUCCUUCCGAGCUUCACAUCUUUCUAAAAUGCAGCUUGGUUUUAAAAUAAAAGAACAUUCAUUUUGUGAUUCUAAACAAGCUUCAGUAAAUACCACCAGUAUAGUACUGGUGAAUUUCUCAGCAUAAAAUCGACAUACCUAAAAAGUUAAUAAAAUUCAGCUCUUUUCCAAUUUCAUUGUUAUGCCUAUUGAAGUAUUAAUUGCCAGGUUUGAUUUUUAGUGAAGCUUGGAGUCCAUACUUUGAGCAGACCAAGUGAAGGGAAGAACAGAAAGAAACUCAGGAGUAGAGUAAUAUCACUUCUCACUUACACCACUUUCAGGCACAUCCAAAGAGUUCCUAGAUACUUGGAAAAUGUCUGAAAAUUUUUAAGUAAAAUACUAAACUUUUCAGUGUUUAGCUCAACUUUUUGUUCAUUUGGAAGUUUCUCUCCAUCCGAGGACUUAAGCCAGUUUUGGAUUUGUAAGCCCUGAGUACAAUACACUUCCUGGAGGCAUCCUCACUGCUGUUGAAGCAAAGGAUAUGCAUGGGGUGGAAGGACGGCUUCGAACCUGGGACUCAUAUGCCUUGAGAACAAAUAGAUUGUUACAGCCUUGGGCUGCUGCGUAAUCACGGUUCCUCGAGGCUCUUCCUGAGCACAUGCCCAAGCAUCUGCCUCUGGAGAGACUGACUCCAAAUGCAGGUGCUUCCAUUGGAGCUAGGUCGGAGGCUGCUUUAUAUGACGAACUCCAGAAAUGGAUGCCAGAAUACGGAGGCCAAACGUUCUGAGUCCUGGUAAGGACAGUCGCUCUGGGGGUCCUCAUUUUACUGCAGUUCCUGCACGCCAGUGAAAGAGAGGAGAUAGACCCUGGAAGGCAGAGCUGCAGAUGCUCAUCAUCAGGUCAAUUCUGGAGCUACAGUUUUGUUUCUGACUGGAUAGGGAUGCACCAGUGACUGUCACAUCAAGCAGUCCUUUUAUUCUCUCUCCUUUAGUAUCGAUUUUAAAGGGCAUUAGGCACUAUGGUUCCAGAGUUUCUUGGGGAAAACUUGCAGAUUCUUAUUAAUUGGUUCUGCAAUACUUAAAUAAAUUAUUUUACAAUUAUAAGUUUUCAGAUUAUAACAUUUGUAUUAAUUUUUACUGAUUUUCCAAGAUACUUCUUAGAUUUACUAUUUACGUAGCUUUAUGUACAUUCUCUGUAAAAAUAGACCUCUAAAUAUGAGGCUUUACAUGAAAUUUGUACACACAUACACACUAAUGUUAGCUCCUUAAAUUGCUGCACUAAGGUGCUGGUUAGUAGAGAUGGACGGAGCCUCUCGCGUUUUGCUCUCAGAUGUGUUAAAGGCGCACGUGUACCUGCUCUCAGCGGCAGUGCGGCCUCCCCAUCUGCUGGGUGCCCAUGGCCCUCCCUGCAGCCUCAGUGAUGACCUCGUCUGCCAGGGACACAGGUUUUCAUCAUUUACAGGCUCUUAUGUGCUAGUUUUGUUGGUAGCACGUUAUUUAAUGCAUAAAGGCAGAAUUCUUACAAGUUUUUUUUUUUAAUGUGAACAUAGAUGCAGCACCGACUUUUUAAACUUGAAAAAACUGGUAUAAUGUUAACUUUUAAAAAUAACAUUUGGACACACUAGUAAUUGAUUUUUGUUUACAGAUUGUUUUGUUUACAAAUUGUUAGUCUUUGUUUCUAUGAGAUACUUUUAGUGUGACUUUUUAAAUGUCUUAGAAAUUAAAAGUUGUACAAAAAGUGAUUUCAUAUUUGGUUUAUAAGCAUUUAUAUGUGGGGUUUAUUUGUUCUUUUGUUUUUUCCAUCUUAAAUAUUAUCAUGGCUAAAACUUAAGGGUAUUUAUAGUUUAAUUCCAUUUCAGUUUUAUAGAGGGCAGUAAUUAUUCUGAUGAAUGUUGAAUUAAGAAAUGGAUAUUUUCUUUCUCUGUUGUGCAGUUAUUGGUAGAUCAAUUUCUUAUAACCCACAAUGUAGCAUCAAUAAUUGAUAGCAUGUAUUUUAUUUAAUUACUUGAAUUAUUUAGACUUGAUUUCUCUAAUUUUUUCCAUAAAAGGACUGAACAGCACCUACUUGUGGUCUGGACAGCUUAACCCAGAGUUCCUGGAAGAAUAAAUGCUGUUAGCAUCUGGUUAAUUUACUGGCAGACAGAAGCCUACUUACAGUGGCUUUCAACUUUUUGACCACAGUAAGAAAUAACCCAUUACACACACACACACACACACACUCUCUCUCUCUCUCUCUCUCUCUCUCUGUCUCUCAGAUACGUAUAAGCAAAAAUUUAACAAGACAGUACUUGUUUUUCCUAAGUGUGCAUGCUGGCAUCUUCUGUUUUAUUAUUUUUAAAAAUACUAGACACAGACACUAAGUUACUUUGUGGCCUCCUAAUAGAUGGCAGACUUCAGUUUGAAAAGCAUCCCUUUGGAAUGUGGUUUAAAAGAAGAAAUAAUACAAAGACCUUUUUGGAGUUUUUUUUUUUUUUGGUUUUUGAAUAUUGUUUAGGUAAAAAUUAUUGCUGCAAACACAACUGAAGCAAAAGUACUGUGUACGCAAAUUACUUGUUGCACUGUAGAAAAUGUAAUAUCAGGAGAAGUUCCUAAAACUCACAAAUAUAUACAAAAUUUCAAAACUUGGUGAUUGAUCCAUAUGUCUUGAAGGAAUAUUAGGCAAUAAACUUACCUUUUCAAGAGAAGUUAUUUAACUUCCAAUUCUGUGUUCUUUAAUUAGGAAAAAAUUUUUUCAAGGUUAACUAUAAUCAAAUAGGAACUUCACACAAAACCUCAUUAUUCUUGGAUAUGGAUUUGGUGUUCUGCUGUUACUUCUAAAGGUGGUACAGAAGUCAAGUUUAUGAGCCUGGAUUAUGAACAGCAGGGCGGCCCUGAUGUGAGUGGUUGUGGAGGACUAGAGUGAUGUAGAAGAAUCUGUUGUGUCUGAGUGUGAGGAGGUGGAGAGUCACGUGUGGGCUAUGGGUCUGAGAACUGAAGUUUUAACAGUUACUAAAACUGUUUUGUGGCUGUUGUAAUGUCUUCUCCUUUCCUUUCCUUUGAAAAGCUGUUACUGAAUGAACGAUGCCGCUUACAAACACUGACACUUCAGAACCAAGCAUAUUUGAUACUGCUGUAGCUAUUUAUAUUGAUUCUGCAACUUCUCUUUAACAGCAUCUUGAAGUCAUCCACAGUUGUUCUAUAUGGACUCCACAGUAGAGUCAGAGAACUAAGUGACAAGUGGAGCAUCGUCCUCCUCCUGCUCACUUCCUCCUCGCCACCUCUCUGGCCUGGCUAUCCUUCAGUCUGAAGAGUGAUUCACUUUUUCUUUUCUUUUUAGUCUUUACUGUGGAAUCUCAUCAAAGACUUGGAAGCAGGGGUGGUGAGAGGGGCCUGGGGCGUGGUGUGGAGGGUCGAGUUCUUUGUCGUCCCACAGUCACCCCCAGGACCACCUUGCGAAGCCGAAAAUACACAUCUGCAUUUUACCGACAAGGAACGCCACUGAGAAAGCUGCAGACAUUUGCCUGGGGUCACGCUUACAGUGGGCAGAUGAACUGGAUGUAAAUACAGGCCAGUACAACCGCAGUCUCAUUUUUUCUUUGUUUUAGGUUUUCAGUUUCUUGUUCAUUCAUGUACCUUACAGUUCUAUUAUCUGGUUGAUAAAGAUUCAUGACAGGUAUCCUCAUUCUAGAUUAUAACCUUUAUUCUUAUCAAAUGCCUCCAGUCCCACAAUUCGCUAAGAAUUCUCUUUCUGGACUUGAUAGUGAUUUAAUGAUUCCCCCCGCCCAUGGAAUGGUAGGCUCCUAAUUAAGUGGAUUUAAAGGCAAAAAGGGAUGUGUGAGAAGGCACAAGAAGUGGCUUCAUCUUGCAAGGUGACUGUCAGACAAGUGGGUUCCAACCUGUUAAAAUAAGGGAGGAAUGGCCACAUCCCGUAGGGACUGCUGUAGCUGACCAGGAAGACACAAUGAGGGCAGCAGACAGGGCUCUCCCUGUCCGCUGAGUCCUCCCAUGAACUCAUGUUUCCAAAGGCCCCACUCUUUCUUGGUCAGUGUCCCAGUUUUUAUAGAAGAGACCUGAUGAGGCUGUGGAGUAAUUGUAUAAAAGCUUGCACUGUUUUCCUGACUUGACCUGACAAUGUGGCGUUAUCUUCAAAUUGUCCAGAGAAGUAGCUACUUCAUUCAGGUCCUUUUUAGCGUUCUGUGGUUGCAACUUGGUCUCGCAAGCUUUCGAUGGGCGCGCCAUUCCAUGGCCACUUUUCAGUAAGAAAAUUGCCUGAUUUUCUGUUAACUGUCACAGGCUGCCCUGGACCAUUCCUCAGAACUCAUGGGAUUUUCGCGACCCUCAUCCUCAGUGAAGUUAGAUGACCAUUCCUGCCUUUCAUCCCACCGAUUUUCCUAAGUAUCUGUUGCCUGCAACUAACACUAGUUCCUGUGUCAGUAAAGUACUGCACUUGGUUGCAAAGAAUAGAGAUGGACUCUGCCAACAUAGGCACGGAAGGUUUACGGGGUGGAUGGCAUGGCUCACAGAUGUGAUGAGAAAGCCCCGGAAGAAGUGUUGGGCACAGCCUUAGGCACAACCUUUCCUGGGCUCUUCCCAUCACUGAAUGAUCCAUGUAUCUCCGGGACUCUCCUUCUAGAUCCAAAGUUUAGGGCGGCGGAAUCGGACUGCUCUGGCCUUUGACACGUGCCUGUGCUUUGCCUGUCAACGCUAUGGGGAGAGAGAUGUCAGCUUACAGAAAAUUGAGGUUCUGUGAUUCAGUUUCCCUCUGCUCUCUUAGAAUAAAAGUGCUUACUCAUUGUUUAAAGCAUUCUCCAAAUUAGUCUGCAAAUUUUUUGAUAGUAUACAUCCUUAAAAAA